GCGCCGCGCCCGGAACCAGCAACGCGGCAAAGGGGUCCUGCACGUACCCGCGCGCGGCCAGGGAACGCUUGCUGAGGGCGCUGCUGUCGUUGGUGUUCUGUACCGCGCCUGCCCGACGCUCACGGCUCCGGGGGCCCAUGGCCAGAAGAGACUCAGGAAUGGCAGUCUGUCACGGUUGUGAGCCGCCCCUUGGUUAGCACACACCUCACGGACCUCGGUGGAAGCAAAUACUGCACAUGCGUGUUGGUCCUGUGAGGGAAACCAGCUAGUGGAGAGGGAGAGGUUGAAGGAACAGAAAAAUGAGAAGACAACUCACUGGAGGCUGAAGUGGGAGGAUCGCUUGAGUCUGGAAGCUUGAGACUGCAGCAAGCUGUGAUCGUGACACUGCACUCCAGCCUGGGCAACAAAGUAAGAUCCUGUCUCAAAAGAAAAAAAAAAAAAGGUGAAGCUGAACCCAGAUCUACACAUACAGCUAAUCUUACCAAAAUGUGUGGAAGUAAAGCAAUCUGAAGGAAAUUCAGUACCAUACAAUUUACUGACUGAAAUACAUCAUAUUGCUCAUACUAAGAAUAAGAGUGGAGAAGAAUCAUUUUUUUCCUGCUAAAAUGAUAGAGGCAGAAGAGCAACAGCCUUGCAAGACAGACUUCUAUUCUGAAUUGCCAAAAGUGGAACUUCAUGCCCACUUGAAUGGAUCCAUUAGUUCUCAUACCAUGAAGAAAUUAAUAGCCCAGAAGCCAGAUCUUAAAAUCCACGAUCAGAUGACUGUGAUUGACAAGGGAAAGAAAAGAACUUUGGAAGAAUGUUUCCAGAUGUUUCAAACUAUUCAUCAGCUUACUAGUAGCCCUGAAGAUAUUCUAAUGGUCACAAAAGAUGUCAUAAAAGAAUUUGCAGAUGACGGCGUCAAGUACCUGGAACUAAGGAGCACACCCAGAAGAGAAAAUGCUACUGGAAUGACUAAAAAGACUUAUGUGGAAUCUAUACUUGAAGGUAUAAAACAGUCCAAACAAGAAAACUUGGACAUUGAUGUUAGGUAUUUGAUAGCAGUUGACAGAAGAGGUGGCCCUUUAGUAGCCAAGGAGACUGUAAAACUUGCCGAGGAGUUCUUCCUUUCUACUGAGGGUACAGUUCUUGGCCUUGACCUCAGUGGAGACCCUACUGUAGGACAAGCAAAAGACUUCUUGGAACCUCUUUUAGAAGCUAAGAAAGCAGGUCUGAAGUUAGCAUUGCAUCUUUCAGAGAUUCCAAACCAAAAAAAAGAAACACAAAUACUCCUGGAUCUGCUUCCUGACAGAAUCGGGCAUGGAACAUUUCUCAACUCCGGUGAGGGAGGAUCCCUGGAUCUGGUGGACUUUGUGAGGCAACAUCGGAUACCACUGGAACUCUGUUUGACCUCAAACGUCAAAAGUCAGACAGUUCCAUCUUAUGACCAGCACCAUUUCGGAUUCUGGUACAGCAUUGCCCAUCCUUCUGUGAUCUGUACUGAUGAUAAGGGUGUUUUUGCAACACACCUUUCUCAAGAGUACCAGCUGGCAGCUGAAACAUUUAAUUUGACCCAGUCUCAGGUGUGGGAUCUGUCUUAUGAAUCCAUCAACUACAUCUUUGCUUCUGACAGCACCAGAUCUGAACUGAGGAAGAAAUGGAAUCACCUGAAGCCCAGAGUGUUACAUAUUUAAGCUAUAAUGAGGUGAACUACUUCUGAGUAUGUGUUUCAAUCAAGUUCCUGCCAUAUCCCACUUAGUAAAACAGUCCACCACUCCUUUGAAGCAUAGCAACCAAGUUCCUUGGGCUCUAUCACCAGCACCUUACACAUGGCAGGUACUCAGUAAAUACGUGUCUUCAACUGACUCACAAGCUCUCAGGUGCUUACUGGGUGGGACUUGACUGUUGUUGCUAAUUAAAUCCCCAUUCCACCAGUGAUUAUUGUGACUCAGCAGUCCUUCCCUAUUAGUGAUCAUAAAAUUUCAGGGAAAUCGAAGUUUCUCAUCAGGAAAUGUUUUGGAAUUACUAGUAUAAAGUUAGGAAAGUGGGGAAAUUAGGUUACUGCCGAGACCUUUAAGCCUUCUAAACAGCUUUAUAUUUUAUUGUGCAUACUUUAAUCAGACUCCCUUCACUCGCUUUAAGUUUUUAAAAGUAUUCCCCAGCCGGAUGUGAUGGCUCAUGCCUGUAAUCCCAGCACUUUGGGAAGCCAAAGUGGGCAGAUUGCUUGAUCCUAGGAGUUCAGUAGCAGCCUAGGCAACAUGGAGAAACCCUGUCUCUACAAAAACAAAAAAACAAAAAACCGGAAAUUAGUCAGGCACGGUGGUACACACCUGUAGUCCCAGCCACCAGGGAGGCUAAGGUGGGAGGAGACCUGAUCCCAGGGAUGUUUGAGGCUGCAGUGAGCUGUGAUGCUACAGCACUCCAGCCUGGGCAACAGAGUGAAACCCUGUUUCAAGAAAAAGAAAAGUAUUCUCCAAGAUCCCAAGACCAUUGACACCAGGCCACAUUGUAUACCAGGGAUUUAUGUGAAUGCCUAGGGAUGACCGUAGUGACAGAUAAAGCUAGGUGCUGAGAUCUGGUUUUGCCCUCUUUAUGAUUGUCCCAUCGGUACUAGAAAGUGAAGUCAUUGCUCCAAUUUUGGAAGAGGAGAGAAUAACUGGCUGAGGGGUGAGAAAGACAGAAAUAGCUGCAGCUCUCUUUUUUUUUUUUUUCAACAAAGGCUCUCACUCUGUUCCCCAGGCUGGAGUGCAGUGACAUGAUCACAGAUCACUGCAGCUUUCAGUUUUAAAACAGCUUUUAUUACAUUUUCUUUGUGGAAGCUGUAUUUCUACCUUAGUACUCACUUUCUGCUUGGUCUGAAAGAUACCUCUAGUAGUGGCAACAUUGUGUUAAGUAGAGUUCAUUGGGUCUCUUGUAACCCUACCCCUACAUAAUGGACCACUGGUGCAGGCUUACAUAAACACACAUACUGUGGCCACUUCAGCUGAAGACAAGGGACAAACUAAGAUAGUUCUGAAAGGUAAAAAAACAAACAAACAAACAAAAAACAAAAACAAAAUUAUUAGAUACCAAGUUAUGCUUGAAUUGCUUUGCUCUUUAGAAUGUGUGUUUUUCCCUGGUAUCAGAAGAAGUUAAGGCUGAUGACACCCCUAAUUUAAAUUACUAAGGAUUUCUGAUAGGUUUUCUGUCUUUCUGUGAUAUCGUAAAGUAUUUAUUUGGUCUUUGACCCUGUUUCCUGGCAUACUGCUCCUAAAAUCCUUAGAGUCUCCAGAGUGAUGGCUUUUUGUAUCUAAUGAGUUGACUGCUGGCUGGCAGCCCCUAGGGGCUGGUCACUGGAAAGACAAAUGCAUGAUUAGAGUUGGGACUUUCAGUCCUCCCCCAAACUCUUGGGAGAAGGGCUGAAGGUUAAGUUGAUCACCAGUGACCAGUGGUAAUCAUACCUUCAUAAUGAAGCCUCCAUAAAACUCCAGAAGAACAGAUUUUGGAGCAUUUCCAGGUAACUGAACAUAUGGAGGUCCCUAGAGGGUGCUGUACCUGAAGAGGGUAGAGGGUAUAGGAGCUCCCUGUCCCUUCCCACAUGCCUUGCUCUAUCCAUUUCUUCAUCUCUAUCCUUUGUACUGUCCUUUAUAAUAAACCAGUGAACCUAAGUGUUUCCCUGAGUUCUGUGAGCUUUACUAGCAAAUUAAACUCAAGGAGGGGUCAUGGGAACCCUGAUUUAUAGGUUUGGUCAGAAGCACAGGUAAAACCACCUGGGGUUUGAACUUGGCACUGGAAGUGGGCAGCAGUCUUGUGGGACUGGGCCCUCAAUCUGUGGGAUCAAAUGCCAUCUCUAGGGGAUAGCAUGGGAAACUGGAGGACACCUAGCUGGUAUCUGCUGCAAAAUUGAUUGCUUGCUUGAUGGUGGGGAAAAAACUCCACACAUUUGGUCAGAGAAGUUUUCUGUCUUUAUUGUGGUGUGAGAGCAGAGGAAAAAAGUUUGUUUUUUCCGCUCAGACUUUGUUUUAAGGAACAGGGGAGAGGGAAGUUCUGUGGUUUUUGAAGUUCUUAGAUACGUGUGUGUAGCUUUGUGUGGCAUUAUAUAUAGCAUUAUAUUAUUUUCUACCCUUAUCUACUCAUACAGAAAUUGCACAGUAAAAACAUCAAAGUUUAUUCAUAAAAUGUGGAUCUAUUGCAGUCACUAAAAAUGUUGCAGAACAGAUUUUAAUGACUGAAAGUGUUCAUGAUAAUAUAUUCAAUGAAAAUAUGGUUAUAAAGUUUUAUAGUCCUUUUUUUGUUUAAUAUCUAUACAAAAGCUAUUGAAGUGUAUGAUUUUAAUUUA